GCUCAGUGCUCUUGAAGCGAGAUUGAAGGGAAAAUUAGAAGCUGUUCAUUUGUGCUUGCGGGCUCAGAAGCGUCGCACUGCUUUGUUUUGUACUCUACCGUGUCCUGUUGAAAGGGGUCAACAAGUGCCGGUGUUCCAGUGUUUUCUCUCAAAACUCUGUGUUUGGAACAUCAAGGAUGGAUUAUCCCAAAAUGGAUUAUUUUCUGGAUGUAGAGUCUGCUCACAGACUCUUGGAUGUUGAGUCAGCUCAAAGAUUCUUCUACAGUCAAGGAGCUCAAGCUCGCCGGGCGACCCUGCUCCUGCCUCCCACAUUAAUGGCGGCAUCCUCGGAGGAUGAUAUAGACCGGCGGCCCAUCCGGAGAGUGCGCUCCAAGAGCGACACGCCGUACCUCGCAGAGGCCAGGAUCUCCUUUAACCUGGGGGCAGCUGAGGAAGUGGAGAGGCUGGCGGCGAUGCGUUCUGACUCCCUCGUCCCAGGCACCCACACCCCACCCAUCCGCAGGAGAAGUAAGUUUGCCAACCUGGGAAGGAUUUUCAAGCCUUGGAAAUGGAGGAAGAAGAAAAGCGAAAAGUUCAAACACACGUCAGCAGCCCUGGAAAGGAAAAUAUCUAUGAGGCAAAGCAGAGAAGAGCUGAUAAAGCGAGGAGUCCUGAAGGAAAUCUAUGAUAAAGAUGGGGAACUCUCUAUAUCCAAUGAAGAGGACUCCCUAGAAAAUGGGCAGUCCCUGAGCUCCAGCCAGCUGUCUCUGCCUGCCCUGUCCGAAAUGGAGCCAGUCCCAAUGCCCAGGGAUCCCUGCUCAUAUGAGGUGCUCCAACCGUCAGACAUCAUGGAUGGGCCAGAUCCUGGCGCCCCUGUGAAAUUGCCUUGUCUGCCAGUGAAACUGUCGCCUCCGCUACCUCCAAAGAAAGUCAUGAUCUGUAUGCCCGUGGGGGGGCCAGACCUCUCACUGGUGUCCUACACAGCCCAGAAGAGUGGCCAGCAGGGUGUGGCCCAGCACCACCACACUGUCCUGCCCUCCCAGAUCCAGCACCAGCUGCAGUACGGCAGCCACGGCCAGCACCUCCCCUCCACCACCGGCUCCCUCCCCAUGCACCCCUCGGGCUGCAGAAUGAUAGACGAGCUCAACAAAACGCUGGCCAUGACCAUGCAGAGGCUGGAAAGCUCUGAGCAGCGGGUCCCCUGUUCCACUUCUUACCACAGCUCUGGGUUGCACUCGGGUGAUGGGGUCACCAAAGCAGGACCUAUGGGCCUUCCAGAAAUAAGACAAGUGCCAACUGUUGUGAUUGAAUGUGAUGACAAUAAAGAAAAUGUGCCUCAUGAGUCAGACUACGAAGACUCUUCUUGCCUGUAUACAAGAGAAGAGGAGGAAGAGGAGGAGGACGAAGACGACGACAGCUCAUUAUACACCAGCUCCCUGGCCAUGAAGGUCUGCAGGAAGGACUCCUUAGCCAUCAAACUCAGCAACAGGCCCUCCAAGCGAGAGCUGGAAGAAAAGAACAUCCUUCCCAGGCAGACGGAUGAGGAGCGGCUGGAGCUGAGGCAACAGAUUGGCACCAAGCUCACCAGGCGGCUGAGCCAGAGGCCAACUGCAGAGGAACUGGAACAGAGGAACAUUUUGAAACCUCGGAAUGAACAAGAGGAACAGGAGGAGAAGAGAGAGAUCAAGAGGAGGCUAACCCGAAAGCUCAGUCAAAGGCCCACGGUGGAAGAGCUUCGGGAAAGAAAGAUCCUCAUCCGCUUCAGUGACUACGUGGAGGUGGCUGACGCUCAGGACUAUGACCGCAGGGCAGAUAAGCCGUGGACCCGCCUCACCGCUGCAGACAAAGCUGCCAUCCGAAAGGAGCUCAAUGAAUUCAAAAGCACUGAGAUGGAAGUUCAUGAAUUGAGUAGACACUUAACAAGGUUAGUAUUAAGGGUUUUUUUUUUCCUUUUUUUCCCUCAAGUUGCAAUAUUUAUCUCCAAAUAAAGCUCUCCCACUUGUGGGACAUGAGUGGGUUGGAGGGUGCCAUGAGAGGGAAGAUAGUAGGAAGGCAGGCAUGCGGUUCCACUUUAGGUUACUGAAACGAGGAAGUGGAACACAGAUGGCCCGGGCUAAAACCAACUUUCUGCAAAGUCUGAGUUUCACUCAUUUAAACUAAAGGUCUGAUAAGCACCAGACUACCAACGACCCCAAGGUGGGUUUUUGUGAAAACUUAGGUCAAGGAGAAAAGAUUGUUGCCAAUUUGCAACCAGUCAGCAGAGGCCAAACCUGAACAAAAUACCACAUCCACACGGGACUUCCAAAGUGGACCACUUCUGUUAUUCCCUGACAUUCUCCCUGACAGUCCAGCAUCAUGAUGAUAUUUGGGAAAACCGAGGCAUGGAGUGAUUAAGAGGAUUAUAUAAGGUUGCAUUGCUAGUUAGCAACAGAGCCAUUGAUUUAAUUCUGACUUUCUUUUGGGGGGAACAUUUAGAGAAAUAGGAUAUAGCAAGUAUUUAGUCUAGAGACUCAGAGACACAGAUUGGGUUCUGCACCUUGCUGCUGGAUCCAGGCUGAUGGCAGGAGGUGGAGGCCACCAGGGCUGCCCCAGAUGAAACUUUCAAAGCCAGGUGUGUGUUCAGUGGUACUCCUGUGGGGAUGACGGUGGGAAGCUCGCACCUCCCUCUCACGGUCAAGAACCUCCCUGAAGAUGGGAGAUUGGACUGUUGAAUCCUGCACCUUUGGCAGCCCCUUGGUCUUGAUGUAAUUGUUUGUUUCCUUAGGUUUCACCGACCUUAACAGUCGAAUUCCUCUUGAGUGCUAUGCUGUCUUCAAAACAUAAAUUUAUAAGAACCAUAAGUGCUGGUAUUUAUUCACUUCCCCAUUACGAUGUAAAUCUUCUGAACUGCCUUUUUUUUAAAAAGAAGAAAAAUCAAGGAAACACAAUCAGGAUUUUAUGUGUGAAAACGCAAAAGUGAUGGCUCGGCGGUCCGAGCUGCUGGUCCCACUUCUGACACCAAAAUGCAUCCCAACCCCCGGCAGUGCCAAGGGCACCAGCAGGGCCCUGACUGAAGACUGUCUGGCAGGUGGAACGGUCCUUGUCCUCUCCAGCCAGGCCCAGCAGGCACUACCUUCAUGAAGUCUCCAGCAAACCUCUUCCUCACAAGUGUCUGUCAUCUGAGUCCAAAGAAAGCUGAAGGGGUGGGUUUGUUUUGGGGGUACUGUGCAAAGCUAAUGAUCUGGUUGGACUUCUACACUUGGCCAAAUGUACUGGCUCCAGACAUGACAUUUGGUUUGGGGGCCCUUUGAAGUUGAUGCCAAGAAGGAGUGAACACUUCUCAGUUGCCCCUGGCUUUUCCCUCCUUUCAGCCACCACCCACACAAUGAACAAAAGGGAAGGGCCCAUUUCUGGGGGAGUCUGGCUGCCUCUUGGCUACGAAGGCUGGCACUGAGCACCCAUCCUGCUCCCUCUGCCUGAGCUGAGCUGCCUUUCAGGAAGCUCUGGUUUAGAAGGGGAAAGAUGUCAUAUGCUCAGUUCAAAUAAUCAACCCAACUGUG